GCUCACAGCCGUCCCUUCGCUGGUGGGAAGAAGCCGAGAUGGCGGCAGCCAGCGCUGGGGCAACCCGGCUGCUCCUGCUCUUGCUGAUGGCGGUAGCAGCGCCCAGUCGAGCCCGGGGCAGCGGCUGCCGGGCCGGGACUGGUGCGCGAGGGGCUGGGGCGGAAGGUCGAGAGGGCGAGGCCUGUGGCACGGUGGGGCUGCUGCUGGAGCACUCAUUUGAGAUCGAUGACAGUGCCAACUUCCGGAAGCGGGGCUCACUGCUCUGGAACCAGCAGGAUGGUACCUUGUCCCUGUCACAGCGGCAGCUCAGCGAGGAGGAGCGGGGCCGACUCCGGGAUGUGGCAGCCCUGAAUGGCCUGUACCGGGUCCGGAUCCCAAGGCGACCCGGGGCCCUGGAUGGCCUGGAAGCUGGUGGCUAUGUCUCCUCCUUUGUCCCUGCGUGCUCCCUGGUGGAGUCGCACCUGUCGGACCAGCUGACCCUGCACGUGGAUGUGGCCGGCAACGUGGUGGGCGUGUCGGUGGUGACGCACCCCGGGGGCUGCCGGGGCCAUGAGGUGGAGGACGUGGACCUGGAGCUGUUCAACACCUCGGUGCAGCUGCAGCCGCCCACCACAGCCCCAGGCCCUGAGACGGCGGCCUUCAUUGAGCGCCUGGAGAUGGAACAGGCCCAGAAGGCCAAGAACCCCCAGGAGCAGAAGUCCUUCUUCGCCAAAUACUGGCACAUCAUCCUGGGGGGGGCCGUGUUGCUCACAGCCCUGCGUCCUGCUGCGCCAGGGCCCGCGCCACCGCCACAGGAGGCCUGAUGGAUGUACAUCAUUCCCGUCGUCCUGUUCCUCAUGAUGUCAGGAGCGCCAGACACCGGGGGCCAGGGUGGGGGUGGGGGUGGGGGUGGUGGUGGGGGUAGUGGCCGGUGAGGGCCCAGGCUGGUCAGCGUCCCGUCUUGCACACCCAGGGGCCUCCCUUUCUGCUGGAGUCCCCUGUGUCCUCAGCCAUCCCAAGAAGGGUUUGCUGGUCCCUCCUUUCCCCCCGUCCCACGAGGCCACCUGGGCCAGCCCCUUGUCCUCUGCCUUCUGCUGGCAGAGGAGCAGCUGGACUGGGGCCUUUGGCACAGCAGCCGGUGUCUCCUGCGCCCGCCUCCCCCAUGGCCCCAUGCAGCCCCAGGGGCUUCCCCCCUGCCCAUGGAGUAGAGCCCGAGAUCCUGGCCACUAUGCCAGUUCUGACCUCGCAUCCCCCUACCCCGAGCCCAUGCAGUCUGGGAACAUGCCGCCUUCUCUCCAGCCUCUGUGCCUUUGUUCCAGGUGGUCUCACCCUCCUGUCCCUGGCUGGGCUAGGUGGUCCUGUCCAGGCUCCUGCAGCGCCCCCCUCACUUUGACACUGGACUAGGAUGCAGCCUCCCUUCUGUGUCCCCUUGAGGGUACCCUGGGUCCCCUCAUCAGGGGCAGAGGCAUGAAAGAGUCGGGGCUGGAUGGCCGGGGGCUUCUGGGCCCGACGCCUAGUGCAGCCCCUGGGGUCGUGGUUUGACAUUUGUCUGCCUGGUGCAAACAAGGAAUCCUUGCCUUUAAGGUGACAGGCCCUCCACAGGCUUCCAGACUUGAAGGAAAAGGUUUAAGAAAGAAAACAAAACCAACAGUUAGUGGAGUCAAAGCCCAGACACUGUAAAUAGAACCCCCUCCACCACCCCCCGCCGCCCAGCAUCCUACCUGGACUGCGGUGCUACGAGGGCCUGCGGGCCUUUGCUGUGUGCCACCCUCCCUGUAAGUCUAUUUAAAAACAUCGACGAUACAUUGAAAUGUGUGAACGUUUUGAAAAGCUACAGCUUCCAGCAGCCAAAAGCAACUGUUGUUUUGGCAAGACGGUCCUGAUGUACAAGCUUGAUUGAAAUUCACUGCUCACUUGAUACGUUAUUCAGAAACCCAAGGAAUGGCUGUCCCCAUCCUCAUGUGGCUGUGUGGAGCUCAGCUGUGUUGUGUGGCAGUUUAUUAAACUGUCCCCCAGAUCGACACGCAGCUAGCCUCCUGCAUUGUAUGGUUAUAAAUAGCACCCUAGUGAGUGCUGUCGUCCAGUCUCUCUUGGGUGUGGUUUGAAUGAUCUCGGGAUGCAUGACUAAAAUGGAAUUACGAUGGCAGAUCGGAAACGCGUUUAUAAACAAGUGAUGGUUUGUGAGUCGACUGUCAAGACCAGGAGGUGGUGCACCGUGGGAGGUUGCCUUCCCUCCCAUCACUUCUUUUUGUUUUUGAGUCAGGGUCUUGCUCUGUUACCCAAGCUGGAGUGCAGUGGCGGUACCUUGACUCACUGCGACCUCCACCUCUCAGGCUCAGCGAUUCUCCCACCUCAGCCUCCUGAGUAGCUGGAAUUGUAGGCGUGCACCACCACGCGCAGCUAGUUUUUGUAUUUUUUGUAGAGACGGGGUUUCACCAUAUUGCCCAGGCUGGUCGUGAACUGCUGGACUCGAGUGAUCCACCUGCCUCGGCUUCCCAAAGUGCUGGGAUUACAGGCGUGAGCCACCGCGCCUGGCCUAUUUUUGGUAACUUUAAUAAAGAAGAUAGUCUUAGCAUUGCUAACUUCUGUUUCUUUCUCCACCUGCAGGAGAUAGCUUAUGCUUUUUCUGUCUUCAUUCCAUGUGAAUCCUGCUUCAUUCUUUUCCUAGAGGAUUCCAGAAAUAUUUACUAAUGCUUUUUUUUUUUUUUUUUUUUUUUUUUUGAGGCAGAGUCUCGCUCUGUCAUCCAGGCUGGAGUACAAUGGCACGAUCUCAGCUCACUGCAACCUCCGCUUCCUGAGUUUAAGCGAUUCUCCUGCAUCAGCCUCCCAAAUAGCGGGGAUUGCAGGCGCCCGCCAACACACCUGGCUAAUUUUUGUAUUGUUAGUAGAGACAGGGUUUCACCAUGUUGGCCAGGCUAGUCUUGAACUCCUGACCUCAGGUGAUCUACCUGCCUCAGCUUCCCAAAGUGCUGGGAUUACAGGCAUGAGCCACUGCGCCAGGCCUACUGAUGCUUUUUGGGAAGUGUUCCCAACUUGGAGUCCUGGUCCCUGUGUCUGAUCUGCAGAUGUCUUCUACCCCGGCACUGGGGGAACAUCUUAUUUUUCCUGGGUUAAACAUUGGGAUCUUUAUAAACCUGAUUAUGUCCUUUCCCUCUAAGUCUCGGUUGCUUUCAGGCUGGCAGGGUUACUCUGUUGGGUAUUCCAGGAAAUGCCUGAGCUCCUUCAGGCUCCCCUAGCGUUCUGUUCUUAUUAAACUUUUCUUCCCCGUCUGGCCGGUCCUUGGGGAACCCACUCACUAUUUUAUUUUAUUGACCGGGUUAUCCAGGGAUGAAGUAUGAAACUCAAAAGAUAGAGUAGGUUGGCCAGGCAUAGUGAUUCAUGCUUGUAGUCCCAGCUGUUUGGGAGGCUGAGACAGGAGGAUCGCUUGAGCCCCAGAGUUCGAUGCUUCCUGAGCUGUGAUUGAAUCACUUUACUCCAGCCUGGGUGACAGAGUGAGACCCUGUCUCCAGAAUAGACAAAAGAUGCAGUGGAAUCCACGUCCAGAAACUGUAUGCUCACUCUGGGCUCCAGCACCCACUUCCCCUCCCUGGAGGCAGCCUGAGUUUUCUGUCCCCUGGUAUGCUGCAGAUACUCUCCACAGAAACAAGCAGAUGCACAUGUCAACAGUUUUGCAAGUGUUGCUCUUUUCCCCCACCUUCUUUUGACAUAGCUGGGGCAGUUUCCAUCUCUGGUAUAAGGUGCCAUCUUAUUCCAUCUCUGGUGUAAGAGUGUGUUGCUGGAUUUGAGUAGUUCUAAGCAGCACUGCAGGAGUCCCCCUGUUCUGCUGCAUCAUUUUGCACACAUAUGUGUCUGUGGAAGACAUGGCCCGGUGGGGCCCCACCUUGCUGGGGGAGAGGGAUGUGUGUGUGAUGGUGGUGCAUGCUUCCCCCUUGCUACUCCAGGUGUCUGCCCCAUCCCUUCACCCUGGAGGUUCCAGACAGCCCCUCUUCACCAGCGAUUCCCCAACUCAUCUCCAGCUCAGAUCCCACCCCUGAUCUCCAGACUCAUGGCCCCAGCUGCCUCCUGGGCUCCUUCCCCAGGAUGUGCCUCAGGGGCCACUAAAGGAGCCAGUGCCUCCCACCUGCCCGGAUCGGGUGCUCCUCCAGGGAUCUUUGUUCCAGUGAGUGGUGCCAUCACCUGCCCAACCUCAUGGACCAGAGCACUGCCCUGUCCCAAUCACGUUCUCCUAUGCACCACCAUACCUACCCCUAAAGUUCUUCCUGGCCUCAUCCCGUCACCUCUGUCUCCAUGGCCUUGGUCCCAGCUCAAGCCUCGUCCUCUGCCACCUGGACCAUCGGCCCAGCCUCCUCUUUGGCCUCCCAGCCCCCAACAUCCCCCCCUCAGUCCAUCCCCCUAAUGGAGAGCUUCCUGACACUAGAGCUGACCUCACUACUCCCCUGCUCACAGCCCUCCGCGUGGCCUCUCACCUCCCCCAGGAUAGAGUCCCAACCCAUCCUUCUGUGUCUCCUCCUCUCUGUGUCCACUGUCCUGACCCUAACUCAAUCCUCAUUCUCUGCCUCCUGGACCCUCAUCCUAGCCUCGUGACUUCUGGUCUAAGAUGUGAGAGCACCUGGCAAGGUAAAUGCUCCAGGAGGGGUUGCUCCCUCCCAUUUCCUGCCACCAGAAAAUGUUAUCGGCUGCGUGGCAUUGCGAAAGCCUUCCUCUUCCCAGCCUAGGGUUUCAUGUGGGCAUUUAGGUGCUCCCAGUACAUAGUUGCAUGGCAAACAAUCCUAAAAUAUACAAGACUACAUUUAGUAUUUUGUAAAAUUCUUUACUAACCCCAAAUUGUCUACUGGAAACUAUAGGCUCCUUUUUUUUUGGUGGGUGGGGGGCAGGUGUGUUUGUGGGAUGGAGUUUCACUUGUCACCCAGGCUGGAGUGCAGUGGCUCAAUUUUGGCUCAAUGCAACCUCCACCUCCCAGGUUCAAGCAAUUCUCUUGCCUCAGCCUCCUGAGUAGCUGGGAUUACAACCGUGUGCCACCACACCCAGCCAAUUUUUGUAUUUUUAGUAGAGACCGGGUUUCACCAUGUUGGCCAGGCUGGUCUUGAACUCCUGACCUCAAGCGAUCCACCUUAGUCUCCUAAAGUGCUGGGAUUACAUGUGUGAGCCACCGCCCCUGGCCUCUGUAGGCUUCUUUAACCCAUCAGAGAGACUCCCUGGUAAGGAUUAGGGGCUAAUUACUGGUGCCUCUUCAGCUGUCAGUCCAUCCUCCUUUAUUUGUACCCACCUUCCAGUCAGCAAGGCACAACAAUGUUGUUACAAAGGAAACAAACUCAAUUUGGCCCAUUUCCUGGAAAUGCAAUCUCCCAAACAGGUUUGUGUGAACCAAAUUCCAUUUUCCUUUGUUUCCCAUGUGCAGUCCCAGUUGCAUUUCCAUGGGAGCCAAUCCACCCACCCAUAGAAUGACUUGAAAAUGUGUGAAGUUCAGAAGUUUCAUACCAAGAAGUUUGCUGAGCAUGAUGUUUGUAUAUUGAUUAGGAGUAAAAAUGUUCAUUUUUACAAAAUAUUACAACUUCUCCCUCUCCCCUCCUUCCACCCAGUAUCCCCUGUUCCUCCCCCAGGCAUUCUGGUCACUGUUCCUUUUUGUUGAGAUCAUUCUCGGUGUCUCAUAUAGCUGGGUUGCAGCUCCGUUCUUUGCCAGGAGGUGGUAAUAGAGGAUUCCACGCACUCAGAAUGCCUCAGGCCGGCGCCUGUGGCUUCUCUCAAUGGAGGGAAGUGUCCUGCAGGGGGCGCUGUUGGUCCUUCAGGCAAGGUCGGGUUCCCUCGAAGUCUCUGUCUUAGCAGUUGCUGGUCUUCAGAAACAUUGGGCACCAAUUUUCUCAUUUCUGAAAUGGAAUUCAGGUGAGGUCCCCUCAGUGCUGAGGUGCUUCAUGUUGUCAGAGGAAGAGUUGGGAAGGGAGCGGAAUGGAGCAGAAAGGCGUCAUCCGCUGCUCACUGAGCUCAGAUAGGAGGCCAGGGAUCGGCAGAUUCAGGAGCCCACUCCUGGCCAACCCCAGGGGCCCCACCCAGUCCUGUCCCUGCUCCUUACGUGCUGUGUAUCUUUAGGCAAGUUGCUUCCUGUCUCUGAGCGUCGUCUUUGUUUCCGCCUUCCUGGGCCUACGGCAGGCCUGAUUCCUCCAGGCAGUGUCCAGAGUUCCGGACAGAUGGAAAAGGAAGAGAGAAUGGGUGUCACAAAGGUCUGUCCACUCCUGGGCCUCAGGCUUGGGGGCCCUGCUCAGGGCUAGCCUGUUUGGGCCUCGGUAUGGACUCCUGCCUCCUGGUCAGGACCUGGAAACCUGGGAGCAGGCAAGGCAGGAACAGGAGAGGGAGGCAAAGGCCCACCAGGCAGGGAUGCAGGGGCCACCUGGAGACGGAGGAGACGGGGCUCCCGGGAGGGAGGCCAGUGGGAGUGAGAGCUUGAAGGAGAGAGAGCCAGGAGAGGAGACAGGUCCAGAGAGGAGGGAAAGGAAAGGACAGGGCAGAGACAGAGAAACCAGAGAGAGGGAAGGAAGAGAGACCCAAGGGGGAGAGACAGGGAAGGAAGAGGGAGGUGAGAAGAGGAAGAGGCAGAUUCAGAGGAGAGAGGAGAGAAAAGAGGUGGAAAUCAAACAGGAGAAAGAGGGAGGAGAGGAGGGAGGAGAGAGUGUAGGAAAAAAGCAGGAGGAAAGAGCCGGGCACGGUGGCUCACGCCUGUAAUCCCAGCACUUUGGGAGGCCAAGGCAGGCAGAUCACGAGGUGAGGAGAUCGAGACCGUCCUGGCUAACACGGUGAAACCCUGUCUCUACUAAAAAUACAAAAAAAAAAUUAGCAGGGCAUGGUGGCAGGCGCCUGUAGUCCCAGCUACUCGGGAGGCUGAGGCAGGAGAAUGGCGUGAACCCUGGAGGCGGAGCUUGCAGUGAGCCGAGAUUGCGCCACUGCACUCCAGCCUGGGCGACAGAGCGAGACUCCGUCUCAAAAAAAAAAAAAAAAAAAAAAAGAAAAGAUGGCCAGAGCAGGAGGGGAGAGAGGAAGAGGGAGAAAGAAGGAAACAGUGUAGGGGGUCAGAAGUGGAAAGAGAAGAAAAAACAGAAGAGGAAAGAAAGACGAGGGGGUGAAAAAAGGGACAGGAAGGAAGAGAGGGAGAGGGUGGGUGCCAUGGCUGGUGAGCUCGGAGAAGAGGGAAGCAGAGAAACGGGUGAAGGAGGGAGCGUCCUAGGGAGAAGUGGGUGGGGGAGAGGGUGUUGGGGGAGAAGAGGGUGGGGGAGAGGGGGCCCCGGGAGAGGGAGGGAUGGAGGAGCGGGGAGCUCCAGCCAGAGAAGAGGAAAGAGAAAGGAGAGAGCUAGGAACUGGGAAGGAAAAGAGCUAGGAGGAGACCAUGAGACAGAAAGAGAAGAGGGUGAAGAGAGAGGAUAGUGGCUGGGAGGAGAGAGGAGGAGGGAGGAGCACAGAGGGAGAGGAGAGGAAACAGCCAGAGAAUCUGCUAGAAGGGAGAGAGGAGAGAGAAGAGCCGGACAGGGAGAGCAGAAGUGAGAAAAAGGAGGGUGGCCACAGAGAGGACAGCGAGAAAAAGAGAACAGGAAGAGGGGAAAAGAGAAGAAAUGGGAGAGGGAAGAAGGGUGGGAGAGAAAACGGAACAGAGAGGGGGCACAGACAGCGGACUGGACCGAGAGGGAGAUGGAGCGGUGCGGAGGGGGAGAGAGAAAGAGGGAGGGAAGGAGGGUAGGAGAGGGCUGGAGAUAGGGGAAAAGAGAAAAGGAGGGUAGGAGAGGGCUGGAGAGAGAAGGGAAGUUAAGAAGGGAAGGAGAGAGACAGACAUUAGGGAAGAAGGAAAGGAGAAAGGAAAAAAUACAAAAAAGGGCAGAGAGAAAAGAACAGGCCGGGCAUGGUGCCUCGCACCUGUGGUCCCAGCACUUUGAGAGGCUAAGGCAGGAGGAUCACUGGAGCCUGGGAGGUGGAGGCUGCACUACUGCACUCCAGCGGGUGAGUGAGCGAGAAAAAAAGCAGAAAGGAAAGAAGAGGUGCAUGAGUGUGGAAGAGCAAUAUGGAGAGAAAGAAGGGAGAGAGGAUUGGAAGUAGCGACAGAGGACCAUGCCCCUCCAGCUGAGGAGGGGGCGCCCCUAAGACAGCGUCAGCCCAGAGACCGGGGCAGGAAGCAGGAACGUGAAGCAGGUUAGGAGCCAGUGUGAGGCACGGAGAGGGCCGGGUAGCUGGGCGGCGGGGGUGUCGUGGGCACAGCCCAGGCUACUGCGGGGACAGGCUGCCAGACCCGGCGGGUCCAGGUUGGGAACUCGGCCAUGCAGCAGAAACGUUCCCUGCCUCAACAGGGCGCAGCCACCCCGGGGCCAUCUCUGUGACCCAGGGAGAGAAAGGACAACGAAUGGGACUAGACGAGGAUGGGGAGGAACAGAGCAGCUGUGGAAGGUGCGGCAGAGAAGGGCCCAGGAGAAAGGAGGAAGGGAAGGAGCUGGAGGGGCGGGAGAACAGGAGACAGAACAGGACAGAGACAGCUGCCCGGGAGGAUGGGAGAACAGAAAGAGGGAGGAAACGCCGAGCACUGACCUGGGGGAGGGGAGUAAAGAGAAGUGAAGGGGGAUUGGAAGGGAACUGGAGAAUGAGAGAAGCAACAGGCGGGGUGCGUGUAGGAGGGCGGGAGAGCCAAUGACAAGACAGAAAAGGCAGAGAAAGCAAAGCAAGACCAGACUCCUCAUCCGGUAACACUGUGUCAGGUCAUUGCCCUCCCACCCCGCCCCCAACCCCAUAACUGAAAACAAGUAGGAACCUGGAUAAAAUAGUCUUAACAAUUUUUUUUUUGAGACGGAGUCUUGCUGUGUUGCCCAAGCUAGAGUGCAGUGGCGCGAUCUCGGCUCACUGCAAACUCCGCCUCCCGGGUUUAAGCGAUUCUCCUGCCUCAGCCUCCCAAGUAGCUGGGAUUACAGGGGCCCGCCAUCGUGCCUGCUAAUUUUUGUAUUUUUUAGUAGAGACGGGGUUUCACCAUUUUGGCUAGGCUGGUCUCGAAUUCCUGACCUCAUGAUCCGCCCACCUUGGCCUCCCAAAGUGCUGGGAUUACAGGCGUUGAGCCACCGUGGCCGGCCCUUAAAAGCAUCAAACUACAUACAAGACCGUAAGGAAGCUGUGGGUCAACGCGGAGGGACGUGGGAACCCAUCCCGGUGAAGCGGCAGCGUCACGUCCUUUCUCCCAGGGAUCUGUUGGUCGGAGACAUCUGGACUUUCAUGUGGACAGCCUGAGUGACAGGGGGACCCAGGGGCCUCACCUGGGCUACCUGGGGUGGGUGGACCCUCCACUGUGCCAAGGUGCAGCCUGGGCUCGGAGGAACAUGCCCUCCGCCUAGUCCCUGACAUCCUUUUCACAUCCAACACGCAGAGCAGGGGCGUGAGGGAGCAGGCAAGCAGGGAAGGGAAAGACAAUGAGCAAGAGCCAGCGGGACGGUGGGGCGGAUGGCAGAGGCUUCGCUGCUGGAAAAUCAGACGCAGAGUACGAAACGCCUGUGCUCACUAUGUUAAUAAUAAUAAUAAAAGGCAAAAAACCAGG